GGUAGAGUGCGCCGUCCAGGGCUAGAGCAAGCGCGGCCCCGCGGCCCGGAGCCAUGCUGAGGAGCUGCGCCGCGCGCCUCCGCACGCUGGGGGCUCUGUGCCUGCCGCCAGUAGGCCGGCGCCUGCCGGGAAGCGAGCCGCGACCCGAGCUGAGGUCAUUUUCUUCUGAGGAAGUCAUUCUUAAGGACUGUUCUGUCCCCAACCCCAGCUGGAACAAGGACCUAAGACUGCUCUUUGACCAGUUUAUGAAGAAAUGUGAAGACGGCUCCUGGAAACGUUUGCCUUCAUAUAAACGUACACCUACUGAAUGGAUUCAAGACUUCAAAACCCAUUUUCUUGACCCAAAGCUUAUGAAAGAAGAACAAAUGUCACAGGCCCAGCUCUUCACCAGAAGCUUUGAUGAUGGCCUGGGCUUUGAAUACGUGAUGUUCUACAAUGACAUUGAGAAAAGGAUGGUUUGCUUAUUUCAAGGAGGCCCUUACCUGGAAGGACCACCUGGAUUCAUUCAUGGAGGUGCCAUUGCAACCAUGAUUGAUGCUACUGUUGGUAUGUGUGCAAUGAUGGCUGGGGGAAUCGUCAUGACUGCCAAUCUCAACAUCAAUUAUAAAAGACCUAUCCCUCUUUGUUCUGUUGUUAUGAUAAAUAGCCAACUUGAUAAAGUUGAAGGAAGGAAAUUUUUUGUUUCCUGUAAUGUUCAGAGUGUUGAUGAGAAGACCCUAUACUCAGAGGCGACAAGCUUAUUUAUAAAGCUGAAUCCUGCUAAAAGUCUGACAUAAAGAGCUGCUGGUGAACUCCAUCUCAUUCUCGCCCCUCCAGAAGAAGCAGUUGUCCCCCAAAUACUCUGCUCCCUCACUGCUGAAUCCCUGUAGGGAGAAGCCUGCCAACAGUGACCUUCCGAAACAGCCUUCUGAAUACAAAGAGGAUUCAGUUUCCAUCUUCUCAACUUUUUAACACAGAAAUACUUCCUGCGAGCAUAUCGACAACUCUCGGGCCAGGCGCUGUGGCUCACACCUAUAAUCCCAGCACUUUAGGAGGCCGAGGCAGGCGGAUUGCCUGAGCUCAGGAGUUCAAGAUCAGUCUGGGCAACACGAUGAAACUCCGUCUCUACUAAAAUACAAAAAAUUAUCCAGGCAUGGUGGCGUACGCCUGUAGUCCCAGCUACUCAGGAGGCUGAGGCAGGAGAAUUGCUUGAACCCAGGAGGAAGAGGUUGCAGUGAGCCAAGAUCAUGCCACAUCACUCCAACCUGGGCAACAGAACAAGAACCCAUCUCAAACAAACAAACAAACAAAAAAAAAAAACUCUUGUCUCCUUAGGAUAUGUUACCUGCUCCACUGCAGACUAGAGAAAUAAAUGUGUAUUGAACCUUUUACUGCAAACUUGAAAAUGCUAGAAAACCAAGCAUGAAGAAUAAAUACAUGGUGGGAAACACACAGGCAUGUGCAUAUGCAUAUACAUUGUAAGUUAGUAAGUUAGAAAGCUAGCUUUGUUGUAUCUGAACACAUGAAUCUUUUUUGGUCAGUGUAGGAAGCACAGCCAGAUCCUAUAGGAAUGAAUACCUCAAAUCUGUUGUCUGAGAUUCUAGAGAUUAAACCACUGUGCCAUUUUUAACCCAGGCUGUACUGUUGUUUCUUACCAACAGCAUAGGUUUUCAUCACUGGAAGGAGCCUGUGUUCAUUUCCUAGGGCUGCUGUAGCAAAGUAGUACAAACUGGAUUGUUUAAACCAACAAAAACUCAUUGUCUCUCAGUUCUGGAGGCCAGAAGUUCAAAAUCAAGGUGUUGACCAAGGCCAUUCUCCUGAAAGUGCUAGGGAAGGAGCUGUCCACGCCUCCCUCCUGGCUUCUGGGAGCCUCAGGUGUUCCUUGGCUUCUAGAUGCAUCAUUCCAGUCCUCCAUCUUCACAUGGCAUUCCCUCUGUGUGUCUCCACAGUGUCUUCCCUCUGUGCAGAUCUAUCUCUGUGUCCAAGUCUCCUCUUUUUAUAAGGAAACCAGUCAUAAUGGACCCACCUGAAUGACCUCAUUUUAACUUGAUUACCUCUGUAAAAAAUGUAUUUCCAAAUAAAGUGACCUUAUGAGGUAUUGGAGAUUAGGACCACAACAUACCUUUUUUGGGAGGACACAAUUCAACCUGUAAAAGAGCCUCAACAAAACUAAAAAAUGAACGGAGAGUUGAAGGGGGCCAGCCCCUCCACACCUGUGGGUGUUUCUCAUCAGGUGGGAUGAGAGACUGAGAAAAGAAAUAAGGCACAGAGACAAAGUAUAAAGAAAGAACCCUGGGCCCAGGGGACCGGUGCUCAGCAUACAGAGGACCCGCACCGGCCCCAGUCUCAGCUCUCUCAGUAUUUAUUGAUUACUGUUUUCACUAUCUCGGCAAGGGGAAUGCAGCAGGAGAACAGGGUGAUAGUGGGGAGAAGGUCAGCAGGAAAAUCUGUGAGCAAAGGAAUCUGUGUUACAAAUAAGUUCAAGGGAAGGUACUAUGCCCAGAUGUGUACGUAGGCCAGAUUUAUGCUUCUCUCCACCCAAACAUCUCAGUGUAGCAAAGAGUAACAGCAGCAUUGCCGCCAGCGUAUCUUGGCUCCAGCCACAGGGUGGUUUUCUCCUAUCUCAGAAUGGAACGAACAUAGGAUCGGGUUUUACACCAAGACAUGCUGUUCCCAGGGGCAUGCAGGAGACAGAGGCCUUCCUCAUCUCAACCACAAGAGGCCUUCCUCUUUUACUAAUCCCCCUCAGCACAGACCCUUUGCGGGUGUCGGGCUGGGGGAUGGUCAGGUCUUUCCCUUCCCGGGAGGCCAUAUCUCAGGCUGUCUCAGUGGGGGGAAACCUUGGACAAUACCCAGGCUUUCUUGGGCAGAGGUCCCUGCGGCUUUCCACAGUGCAUUUUGCCCCUGGUUAAUUGAGAAUGGAGAAUGGCGAUGACUUUUACCAAGCAUACUGCCUGUAAACAUACUGUUAAUGAGGCACGUCCUGCACAGUCCUAGAUCCCUUAAACCUUGAUUCCAUACAGCACAUGUUUCUGUAAGCACAGGGUUGGGGCUAAAGUUACAGAUUAACAGCAUCUCAAGGCAAAGCAAUUUUCUUAGAACAGAUCAAAAUGGAAUUUCUCAUGUCUUCCUUUCUACAUAGACACAGUAACAGUCUGAUCUCUCUUUUCCCUACAGAGACUAAUGUUCUGGAAAAUAUAUUCUGCUUCCUAGUGCAGGCAAUAGAUUAUUUGGGCUUCCAUUUCUUUCCUUUCUUUCCCCAUAUUAGAAAUUUAAGCUGAACCAUAUGAAAUCACUAUUUCGAAGAACAGAAUGGUCAAAUAUUGACAAUUUCCUAUGGUUCAACCUAAUAACUUAGGGACAGCCUUGUGGUACCCUACCCAGUCAUCCUUCCACAGCCAAAAGAUCAGCUGGAGCCCUCCAUUGCCAGAGCUGACUGACCUGGGAUGGCCAAGCCAGAGGAAGACCCACAUCCUGGAAGCCCUGUCUCUAGUGCCCAACUCCAGUUCUCAAGUUGCAAGGGCCCAGCAGACAUGGGGGCACUGCAGGGGUGAAGCUGGCAGUUCCUUCUCCCAGAAAUUCUGAGAGAGCCUGGGAAAGUGCCCCAGGAGAUGGCUGGGCUCACAGCUCUACAAGUUACAGGUCUGGCAAUGGCCACCCUCUAUUCCCAGUCUUCCAACAAAUCCUGAAACUUAAGAGAGUGGACUCUUACAAUAAUUAUAUUUCACAUGUUAAAAAAUAUGACUCCGAAGGAAUAAGCCAGCGCUGCUCAUUUAGCUAGUUUCACUUAACUAGUUGGGAGGAAGUUUAGACAAUGAAGGUACUGUACUCUCAUCGUUAGAUUUCUCUGGCAGGCUUGCAGAACUGCUAUGGCACACCAGACCUCCAGCCAAGUGAAAGAACCUAACUGAAAGAGUGCCAAAUGACCAGGUUUUCUUCAUGUUAAGUAUGCCUGCCUCCCUUCGUAUCCACUUUUUUCCCUUUACAGUUUCAUUUCUUACACUGGUUUGCUCACAUCCAGGUUAGAUGCUGCACAAGAUCAACUAAGGAAAAAGCUCAGUCACUGUUAACAUAGGGUUCCCCAUAGCCAGUGAGGGAAAAAUGGCUUCCCUGCUUUGCAGCAGACUAUUCCUAGCCUUCACCAUGCCCUGGCACUCUUGCUUUCCUCAGGUUGUAUUUUGACAAGUAUGUAAGAUAACAAAAGGUGGCAGAACAGGUAGAAAGAAGGAGAGAGAUGCUAUCAGAAUUGCCAGCUCCACUCCAUCACUGGCUUGCUGUGUGACCUAAUGGAACUAUUCCUCAUUUCCUGUUUCCUUCUUUUUCCUUUCUUUUUUCUUUUUCUUUUUUUUUUUUUUUUUUCAAGACAGGGUCUGGCUCUGUCGCCUGGGCUGGAAUGCAGAGACACAAUCUCAGCUCAAUGCAACCUCCACCUCCCAGGUUCAAGCGAUUCUCCUGCCUCAGCCUCCCAAGUAGCUGGGACUAUAGGCAUACACCACCAAACCCAGCUAAUUUUUGUAUUGUUUGUAGAGACAGGGUUUUGCCAUGUUGCCCAGUCUGGUCUCAAACUCCUGGGCUCAAGUGAUCUGCCCACCUCAGCCUGCCAAAGUACUGGGAUUACAGGCAUGAGCCACCUUGCUCAACCUGUUUCCUUCUUUAUACCAAGUGCUAACAUUUUGAAUGAAUAUUAGGAAUUGAUGCUGGUUAGUGCUAAAAUAUCUUUAAACUAUCAGUGUAAACAUAAUUAGGCCGUGAGUUUUUGCUCUUACUCCCAGGUUUCUAAAUGUCUAAGAAACAAUAAAAUGAGAGUCAUGUACAGAAA